AGCACAGGACACAGCUAGGUUCUGAAGCUUCUGAGUUCUGCAGCCUCACCUCUGAGAAAACCUCUUUGCCACCAAUACCAUGAAGCUCUGCGUGACUGUCCUGUCUCUCCUCGUGCUAGUAGCUGCCUUCUGCUCUCUAGCACUCUCAGCACCAAUGGGCUCAGACCCUCCCACCGCCUGCUGCUUUUCUUACACCGCGAGGAAGCUUCCUCGCAACUUUGUGGUAGAUUACUAUGAGACCAGCAGCCUCUGCUCCCAGCCAGCUGUGGUGUGAGUAUCAACCCCUGGCUGCCCUGGGAGGCAAGGGUGAGGGCUGGAUUUUUAAAGGGGGCCUGUUUUGGGGAGGGGGUGAUGAGCGUUGGGGAGGCAGCUCUCAGGGCUGAAGCCUUCCCUGACAGCAGUGAGGUCACAGGUCAUGAACUCACUUUUCAAGUGCUGAAGGCGGCUGAGUGGCAGCCGAGACAGAAGGGGGUUCCUGGGGAGGAAGUUAUUCAGAGGACAGGGAAGCAGGGGAAGGCAGACAGGUCCCGUGAGAUAUGGACCAAUUCCUUAAACCAUGCUAGAAAAACAUGUGGAAAAGUCACUACCAGGCUGGCAGGGAAUGGGGCAAUCUAUUCAUACUGAUUGCAAUGCCCACUGGUUCCUAAUCUGGGCAACCCCUGGGGCCCACAGCUAAAUCCAGUGAGUGGAAGUUACAGGGAGUCUGCUUCCAGUGCUGCUCCGGGAAGGAUCCCAUCCACCAGAGCUGCCCCACAUGGACCAUGGUCAGGCAGAGGAAGAUGCCUACCACAGGCAAGGGAUAAAGCCAGAUGACCUCAAAGGUCCCAUGGGAUUCUAAUCUGUCUGCUCCUUGUUCUACGGAUUCCAAACCAAAAGAGGCAAGCAAGUCUGCGCUGACCCCAGUGAGUCCUGGGUCCAGGAGUACGUGUAUGACCUGGAACUGAACUGAGCUGCUCAGAGACAGGAAGUCUUCAGGGAAGGUCACCUGAGCCUGGAUGCUUCUCCAUGAGCCGCAUCUCCUCCAUACUCAGGACUCCUCUCCGCAGUUCCUGUCUCUUCUCUUAAUGUAAUCUCUUUUAUGUGCUGUAUUAUUGUAUUAGGUGUUAUUUCCAUUAUUUAUAUUAGUUUAGCCAAAGGAUAAGUGUCCCCUAUGGGGAUGGUCCACUCUCACUCUUUCUCUGCUGUUGCAAAUACAUGGAUAACACCGUUAAUUCCAUGUGUUUUCAUAAUAAAACUUUAAAAUAAAAUGCAAA